AGUCGGUGGCUCGGGCGCCGGCGGGGAGCUGCUCGGCGGCGGACAGUGUAAUGUUGGGUGGGAGUGCGGGACGCCUCAAAAUGUCUUCCAGUGGCACCCUCAGCAACUACUACGUGGACUCGCUUAUAGGCCAUGAGGGCGACGAGGUGUUCGCGGCGCGCUUCGGGCCGCCGGGGCCAGGCGCGCAGGGCCGGCCUGCAGGUGUGGCUGAUGGCCCGGCCGCCACCGCCGCCGAGUUCGCCUCGUGUAGUUUUGCCCCCAGAUCGGCCGUGUUCUCUGCCUCGUGGUCCGCGGUGCCCUCCCAGCCCCCGGCAGCGGCGGCGAUGAGCGGCCUCUACCACCCGUACGUUCCCCCGCCGCCCCUGGCCGCCUCUGCCUCCGAGCCCGGCCGCUACGUGCGCUCCUGGAUGGAGCCGCUGCCCGGCUUCCCGGGCGGUGCGGGCGGUGGCGGUGGUGGUGGAGGCGGCGGUCCGGGCCGCGGUCCCAGCCCUGGCCCCAGCGGCCCAGCCAACGGGCGCCACUACGGGAUUAAGCCUGAAACCCGAGCGGCCCCGGCCCCCGCCACGGCCGCCUCCACCACCUCCUCCUCCUCCACUUCCUUAUCCUCCUCCUCCAAACGGACUGAGUGCUCCGUGGCCCGGGAGUCCCAGGGGAGCAGCGGCCCCGAGUUCUCGUGCAACUCGUUCCUGCAGGAGAAGGCGGCAGCGGCGACGGGGGGAACCGGGCCUGGGGCAGGGAUCGGGGCCGCGACUGGGACGGGCGGCUCGUCGGAGCCCUCAGCUUGCAGCGACCACCCGAUCCCAGGCUGUUCGCUGAAGGAGGAGGAGAAGCAGCAUUCGCAGCCGCAGCAGCAGCAACUUGACCCAAACAACCCCGCCGCGAACUGGAUCCACGCUCGCUCCACCCGGAAAAAGCGCUGUCCCUACACCAAAUACCAGACGCUUGAGCUGGAGAAAGAAUUCCUCUUCAACAUGUACCUCACCCGGGACCGGCGCUACGAGGUGGCCAGGAUUCUCAACCUAACAGAGAGACAGGUCAAAAUCUGGUUUCAGAACCGUAGGAUGAAAAUGAAAAAGAUGAGCAAGGAGAAAUGCCCCAAAGGAGACUGACCCGGCGCGGUGCUGGCGGGAGCGCUCAAGGGCAGCGGAUUUGUUGUUGUUGCUGUUUUCCUUUGUGGGUGUUUGGUGCUUGAUUUCCAGAAACUCUCCAGCGACUUGGACUUCUUCUUCUUUUUUUUUUUCUUUUUAGAUAGAAGUGACUGUGUGGUUGGUCUCUGAGGUAUUUGGGGGACUCUGUAUUUGCUCGUUUACGUGUUGGAAAAACCAAGUGGCUUUGGGGUUUCGCCCUAUCCCACUCCCUCUCUUUCCUGCUCCAUUGGUUCCUUAAGAAAUGCUAUAUUUUGUGAGUGCAAGCUGGCUUGGGGAGCCCUCUCUUGUGUAAAUGUCCCCCAUGUUUCUGAAAAGUGCUGUAGUUUAGUCCCCUCACCCCCAGCACUGCCCAAACAGGGGCCAAGUGCGCCCCAAUUCCAAGAAUGAAGGCAGAGCGACAACAGUGCGGACACCCCGGCUGCUAGCCCACGGUGAAGCCCGGCGGGGUUGCCCACCAGUUGCGAAAGCCCCCUUUCCUCAGGGAGCACGCGGGACCUCGGUGGAGAUCUCCAGUGAGGCUUAGAGGAGCCCAGGGCCUCGGGCGGGUUGGGGUUUGUCCUCAGUGCAUUGGACGCGCUGCUCUCUCCCCUGAAGGCUGGGCUCGCGUGGGCGGCCGCGGGUGGUGGCCCUCCCGGUUCCUGCCCGAGGACCAGUUGUAAAUGUUACUGCUUCCUACUAAUAAAUGCUGACCUGAUCAAAUGGAGCCCAGACGCUGGCCCUAAA